CUUUCCCUCUCCGUUUUGGUGGGCUGGUUGAAGAUGAAAUCCACUGAGGAGGGAAGUCCAGCACCCUGUGUGCCAGUCCAGAACUGGCCCAUCUGUAGACCCCCUGAAAAUCAUAUGGGCUUGGAUUUGGAUAUUCUCAACAGAAAGGGUUAAAGGCUGAUGGUACCUAAAGCCUGGUACUUGAAUUUUGAUCAAGAUAAGCUGCCUUAAGUUCUCUUCAUUACACAAAUGAUCCUAGAUAAUUGAUAGAUCCUGUGGUUCAACUGGAUUUCUAGAUAGAAGCUGGAUUCAUGUGAUGCCAGAGGAGUAAAAUUUCAAGAGACUGAAACCAGAUCUGAGUUUCGCUGUUCCAGUCUGGACCUCUUUGGUGCUGUAAAUCCUGGAUAUACUGUAGAUGAGUACUGCGUUUUUCUUUUAUGCCGGAGCUGCGGCCCGCAACUCCCUCAGCCUGGCAGGUCCCAGGAUGCUUCGGGGCAACCCCACGCAUGCGCGCUCUGGCGUAGUUCCCUGAAGCACUCGCUCGCAGAGAAUCCUGGAAUCUUCGCUUGUGGAGCUGUGGAGGCAACGGAGUUUUUCCGCGCUUUUUCUUUCAGCCUCAGAGCCUCUCUUCAGCUUCUGGAGACCUCACUAUCCUAUUAUGUCUUUGUGUGAAGACAUGCUGCUUUGUAAUUAUCGAAAGUGUCGCAUCAAACUCUCUGGCUAUGCAUGGGUCACUGCCUGCUCUCACAUCUUCUGUGAUCAGCAUGGCAGUGGUGAGUUUAGUCGCUCACCAGCUAUCUGUCCUGCCUGCAACAGUACCCUUUCUGGAAAGCUAGAUAUUGUCCGCACAGAACUCAGUCCAUCAGAGGAAUAUAAAGCUAUGGUAUUGGCAGGACUGCGACCAGAGAUCGUGUUGGACAUUAGCUCCCGAGCGCUGGCCUUCUGGACAUAUCAGGUACAUCAGGAACGUCUCUAUCAAGAAUACAAUUUCAGCAAGGCUGAGGGCCAUCUGAAACAGAUGGAGAAGAUAUAUACUCAGCAAAUACAAAGCAAGGAUGUAGAAUUGACCUCUAUGAAAGGGGAGGUUACCUCCAUGAAGAAAGUACUAGAAGAAUACAAGAAAAAGUUCAGUGACAUCUCUGAGAAACUUAUGGAGCGCAAUCGUCAGUAUCAAAAGCUCCAAGGCCUCUAUGAUAGCCUUAGGCUACGAAACAUCACUAUUGCUAACCAUGAAGGCACCCUUGAACCAUCCAUGAUUGCACAGUCUGGUGUUCUUGGCUUCCCAUUAGGUAACAACUCCAAGUUUCCUUUGGAUAAUACACCUGUUCGAAAUCGGGGCGAUGGAGAUGGAGAUUUUCAGUUCAGACCAUUUUUUGCGGGUUCUCCCACAGCACCUGAACCCAGCAACAGCUUUUUUAGUUUUGUCUCUCCAAGUCGUGAAUUAGAGCAGCAGCAAGUUUCUAGCAGGGCCUUCAAAGUAAAAAGAAUUUGAGCCACGCAUAGUGUCACGCACCUGUGAUCCCAGCUACUUAGGAGGUUGAGGCUGGGAGGAUCACUUGAGCCCAGGAGUCUGAGGCUUUAGUGAUCUAAGAUCAUGCCACUGCACUCCAGCCUGGGCAACAGAGUGAGACCCUGUUUCUAAAAAAAAAUAAAGAUAAUUUAGCUAACUUUA